AUGAUGUAUGCUUUGUUUCUGUUGAGUGUGGGUUUAGUAAUGGGGUUUGUGGGGUUUUCUUCUAAGCCUUCUCCUAUUUAUGGGGGUUUAGUAUUGAUUGUUAGCGGUGUGGUCGGGUGUGUUAUUAUUCUGAAUUUUGGGGGAGGUUAUAUGGGUUUAAUAGUUUUUUUAAUUUAUUUAGGGGGAAUGAUGGUUGUCUUUGGAUAUACUACAGCGAUGGCUAUUGAGGAGUAUCCUGAGGCAUGGGGGUCAGGGGUUGAGGUCUUGGUGAGUGUUUUAGUGGGGUUAGCGAUGGAGGUAGGAUUGGUGCUGUGGGUGAAAGAGUAUGAUGGGGUGGUGGUUGUGGUAAACUUUAAUAGUGUAGGAAGCUGAAUAAUUUAUGAAGGAGAGGGGUCAGGGUUGAUUCGGGAGGAUCCUAUUGGUGCGGGGGCUUUGUAUGAUUAUGGGCGUUGAUUAGUAGUAGUUACUGGUUGAACAUUGUUUGUUGGUGUAUAUAUUGUAAUUGAGAUUGCUCGGGGGAAUAGG